GGGUCCGGUUUCCGGCGGGAGCGUGGGCCGCCAGACUCGGGAGAGGCUCCGUCUUGUGCAAGGGUCCUGUGGGCUGGCUGCACUGGCCUCUGCGGUGGUGCCUGCCAGAAUGCCCCACUUGGAAAACGUGGUGCUUUGUCGCGAGUCUCAAGUGUCCAUCUUGCAGUCCUUGUUUGGAGAGAGACAUCAUUUCAGCUUUCCAUCCAUUUUUAUUUAUGGACAUACUGCUAGUGGAAAGACCUAUGUAACACAAACGUUGUUGAAAACUUUAGAGCUCCCACAUGUGUUUGUGAAUUGUGUUGAAUGCUUUACAUUGAGGCUGCUUUUGGAACAAAUUUUAAACAAAUUGAAUCAUCUUAGUUCUUCAGAGGAUGGAUGUUCUACUGAAAUAACCUGUGAAACAUUUAAUGACUUUGUUCGCUUGUUUAAACAAGUAACCACAGCUGAAAAUCUUAAAGAUCAGACUGUAUAUAUUGUUCUAGAUAAAGCAGAGUAUCUAAGAGAUAUGGAAGCAAAUCUUUUGCCUGGAUUUCUUAGAUUACAAGAAUUGGCUGACAGAAAUGUGACUGUUCUCUUUCUCAGUGAAAUUGUUUGGGAAAAGUUUCGUCCAAAUACUGGAUGCUUUGAGCCGUUUGUCUUAUAUUUCCCUGAUUACAGCAUAGGCAACCUUCAAAAGAUCCUGUCCCAUGAUCAUCCUCCAGAGUAUUCAGCUGAUUUCUAUGCUGCCUACAUUAACAUUCUUCUUGGAGUUUUCUACACUGUUUGUCGAGAUUUGAAAGAGCUCAGACAUCUGAAAAUGCAGAACUCCAUAAAAAUCAAAAUGAGGAAUAACAGAAAAGAGAUGUAAAAACUUGAGCAGUUUUACAACUCUGUUAAUAUUUUGUAACAGAUUUUGUUCAAGUUUUAUGUAUGCGGUGAUUGAGGUCUAGAAUCUAGAUGGAUUUGAGUAUGGUCAGAAGCUUUCAUUGCAGGUCUUUCAUUAACCACUGACCCUGAGCUGGUAAUCUUUGUAUAGAUGGUUCUUUUUAAUUUUUUUUUUUUAACAAUUAGAAUAGCUGUUUAUAUUUCAUAGACAGUUUGGAAAAUGUUGAUGUUUAAUUUUUCUUUGACCUUUUUUGUUUUAAUUGUAGGGAUGGGAAAGGAAAGAGACAAGAAUUUCUGUUUUCCCUUUUAGAAAUCUUCAAUUAAUUAAGAUCUUAUCUCCAUUUAACAGAAAAUAGUAAUAUAUCUGAGGCUGGAAAACAGUCACUUUCAAAGUAACAGAUUCUAUGUCUCUUAGCACAUUUUCUUCACUUUGUUCUUUUUCUGUUUUUGCCCUGAAAAGUAUUACUUAGUUUCAGUGUGUGUUUGCGACAGAACACAGAAGGCAAUCAUUUAAAAUUAUGCUCACAUUUAGUAUGUUUUUGAAAGUUUCAGAUUUCAGGGCUCCUCUGAUUUACAUGUAGAUUUCAGACAUCUUCUCAGCUGGGAAAAAACAAAACAGUUUUUCCAGUUCAAGCUUAUCACUAACAUUCCUCUAGAAGUUGGAUGUCUUGGGAUCCCUGGCUUCUGAGGGAAAUGAUAACACAAGAGACUUACAGAGAGGAGAGGGUCAGGAAAACGCACCUGAGUGAGAUGGACUUAGGAGCAGAUAAUCCUCCUCGGUCUUUCCUGGAAAGUAACUUGCAGUUACCACUCUUUAGCACUCGAAUCCUGUGGGAAUCUGUGCUGACAGCCAUUUCAAAGUAGAUUAUAAAGUACAAGAAGGAAAAAUUUAGGGAAAAUAUUUAUGGGAAAAUAAAAUGUAAAGAGAGAAAUAUAUAUUUAAAUGUGGUAUUUUUUAAAGUUCUUCGAGUUUCACUGUGGAAUGAUUUUAUUUAGGGUGAGGUUACAGCUUUUUAAAAAAUAAUAUUCAUAAAUGUGUAGUAUGGUUUAAGUCUUAUACUACUAUUGGUAAUAAUAGAGAAAAGGAUCCUUAAACAUUAGAGAAAAAUAGCACAAUGUUCUUAGUUUUCUCUAUAUAUAGAACAUGGAAGAAUAAAGAUAUUCAUUUUCUUUUUUUUCUUCAGAUAGUGUUGUUUGUGUUUGUUUCAAAGUUUGUAAGUGGCAUAUUUCUUGAAAGUUUAUUAAAUCACCUGAAAAAUAUUCUUUUCAGGGAUCUUUUCUGGAAAGAUGCUUUAUGAAUUGAUAUUUCUGUAUUUUUCAGAGGCUAGUUCUAUAGGUAGCUUAAGAUAGGAGAAAAUGAAGUACUACUUUGAUAUUCAUUUAGGUUUGUUUUCUCUAACAAACCUUAUGAUACUGCCUUUUUAACUGUUAUUCAUAAAUUAUUAAACAUAUUUUAGUGUUUCAACCAAAGAGAAAAUCAAUACAGUUGCCCCUUGGUAUACUUGGGGGAUUGGUUCCAGGACCAGUCCCAUAUAUAUCAAAAUCCUAGCACACUCAAACCCUGCGAUCAACUCCGCAGAACCUGAGUGUAAAAAAGUUAGCCCUCCAUAUACAUGGGUUUUGUAUUCCCUGAGUACUGUUUUUGAUCUGUGUUUGUGAUCUGUGUUUGGUUGGAAAAAAAAAAAAAUCUGUAGACAAGUGGACCCUCACAGUUCAAACCUAUGUCGUUCAAGGGUCAGUUGUUUAUUUUGAUUAGCCAAAUUGUGUACCAGUUGCUGUUAACAUUAUGACACUUUAGUGUUAUUACACCAUGCUUAGAUCUGAAAAUCUAAAAUUAAGGUAAGAAAGUUUGGCUAAAGCGAAUAAUUUCUUUUUGAUUCUUCUUCUCUACACUUAGUAGAAUUUGGAAGAUUUUUCUAUUUUAAAUCAUUGUUUUUUAUGAAGUAGAAUAGGAAGAAAUUAUUUUAAUGAUUUGGUUCUUAGUUUUCUGUUAUCUAGUUAUAUGUUAUAUAGUUACACAUUUAUAUAUAUCUUUUUCUGUGCCUUAUUGAAUUAUUUUGAUAUGAAAUACUUGGGAACAAACUAAUAUAUAUAUAUUUUUUUUAAAUAAAUGGAAUUAGUAUGUUUUUAACCAGUUUGCUUAAACUGCUGUUCAGUAGAAUUCCAGUGUUGAUUCAUGGAAAACUACUAAGUAGUUAUAAUUAGUUAAUUAGUACUCCUCAAACUUUAGAAUACAUAGAGUUUCUAGAGAGAUCGUUAAACAUAGAUUCCUGGGUCUCAUCCUCAGAGAUUCUGAUUUGGUAUGCCUGAGAUGGUGCCAAGAACUUGCAUUUAUAACAAUCGCAGGUAGUGCUGCCAAUCCAAAUACUUUGAGUCAUACGAAACUCAAUGAUGUUUAGUUUAUGAGAAUGUUCAGACCUUAGAAAACAACAGUUAAUUAUUUGUGCUUGAGGUUUUUCAUUAUAUGUUUUAUGGUUCUAUGUGACAUAAAUAUAACCUAAAAGAACAAAUUAUGCUUUGUUACUGUAGGGAAGUUCACAUUUUUACCCUGCAGUUUUGAUAAUUUGAAUCUAUAAAACAAACUAAUAAUAGAUUAACGGGAAAAAAAAGGCAUACAAAUUUAUUUUUUAAUUUUAAUUUAAUUUUAAAUUUAAUUUUAUAUUAAGUUCCAGGAUACAUGUGCAGGGGCGUGCAGGUUUGUUACAUAGGUAAAAUGCGUGCCAUGGUGGUUUGCUGCAUCUAUCAACCCCUCACCUAGGUAUUAAGCCCUGCAUGCAUUAGCUAUUGCAUACAAAUUUAUUAAUAUGCAUAUGGGCACAGGAGCCUUACACAAAAUAUGAGACUCAAAAGGUGGGGGGCAGAAAGGGGGGCCAGCUGGUUCAAAUUUUUAUGACAUCCUGAGGUUACAGAAAGAAAAUGGGCUUGGAGCAUGGCAUAACAGGUUAUUGGAGGGAGAGGAGCAAAGACUUGGUUAGGGAAGGCAGUCUUGUGCAAAUGAAACCUCAUAGGCAGCAACUUUCAGAAAGAAUAGAUGGUAGCCUGUGCUAAGUUUCUCUGUCACACCUUCAAAGGUGUCAGACCCUCAAGUCUCUUUCUUGAGAGUUAAUCUUUCCUAGAUCCAAGGUGGGGGGUGAUCAGAGAAAGCCUGUUUGCAUCUGCUGUUUUCUUAUUUCCUCUACAGAUGCAAAUCUCCCUCACAAAAUACAGCUUUUCAGGGCUGUUCUUGUGCUUGCAGCCCUUCUGAUUAGCCAUAUCAAAAUAUACCAAAGAAGUAUAUUUUUGGUGAGAUGCUCCAUUCUCCUAAUUUUGUAUACAGAGGCUAAUGUAUUAGGCAGAAUUUAGCCAAUUAAGGAAUAUUUUAUGUUGUGCUGUCAUUAUUAGUAUUUUUGCUGUUUUGUUAUUAUAGUAAUAAGCUACAAUUACAUUUUUUUUUAGAAAGAAGCAGGGUCUUGCCAUGUUGUCCAGGCUGGAGUGCAGUGGCUGUUCACAGGUGCAGUCACAGCACACUACAGGCUUGAUCUCCUGGGCUCAAGCAAUCCCCCUGCCUCAGCCUCCUGAGUAGCUGGGAUUACAGGCACAUGCCACUGCGUAUAAUUACAUUUGACUUGAGCAAAUGUGUUAAGUAAAAUUUCCUGAACUGCAAUACAGAUUUUACUUGAAAAAUAAAUUUCUAAUUGUGAUCGA